ACACUCCCUACACCACACCCAUACUCAGCCCCUGCAGGCAAGGAGAGAACAGGUCAGGUUCCCGAGAGCUCAGGAACAUGGAGCUGAUCCAGGACACCUCCCGCCCGCCACUGGAGUACGUGAAGGGGGUCCCGCUCAUCAAGUACUUUGCAGAGGCACUGGGGCCCCUGCAGAGCUUCCAAGCCCGACCUGAUGACCUGCUCAUCAACACCUACCCCAAGUCUGGCACCACCUGGGUGAGCCAGAUACUGGACAUGAUCUACCAGGGCGGCGACCUAGAGAAGUGUAACCGGGCUCCCAUCUACGUACGGGUGCCCUUCCUUGAGGUCAAUGAUCCAGGGGAACCCUCAGGGCUGGAGACUCUGAAAGACACACCGCCCCCACGGCUCAUCAAGUCACACCUGCCCCUGGCUCUGCUCCCUCAGACUCUGUUGGAUCAGAAGGUCAAGGUGGUCUAUGUUGCCCGAAACCCAAAGGACGUGGCGGUCUCCUACUACCAUUUCCACCGUAUGGAAAAGGCGCACCCUGAGCCUGGGACCUGGGACAGCUUCCUGGAAAAGUUCAUGGCUGGAGAAGUGUCCUACGGGUCCUGGUACCAGCACGUGCAGGAGUGGUGGGAGCUGAGCCGCACCCACCCUGUUCUCUACCUCUUCUAUGAAGACAUGAAGGAGAACCCCAAAAGGGAGAUUCAAAAGAUCCUGGAGUUUGUGGGGCGCUCCCUGCCAGAGGAGACCAUGGACUUCAUGGUUCAGCACACGUCGUUCAAGGAGAUGAAGAAGAACCCUAUGACCAACUACACCACCGUCCCCCAGGAGCUCAUGGACCACAGCAUCUCCCCCUUCAUGAGGAAAGGCAUGGCUGGGGACUGGAAGACCACCUUCACCGUGGCGCAGAAUGAGCGCUUCGAUGCGGACUAUGCGGAGAAGAUGGCAGGCUGCAGCCUCAGCUUCCGCUCUGAGCUGUGAGAGGGGCUCCUGGAGUCACUGCAGAGGGAGUGUGCGAAUCUACCCUGACCAAUGGGCUCAAGAAUAAAGUAUGAUUUUUGAGUCAGGCACAGUGGCUCAUGUCUGCAAUCCCAGCGAUUUGGGAGGUUGAGCUGGUAGGAUCACAAUAGGCCACGAAUUUGAGACCAGCCUGGUAAAAUAGUGAGACCUCAUCUCUACAAAGAUGUAAAAAAAUUAGCCACAUGUGCUGGCACUUACCUGUAGUCCCAGCUACUUGGGAAGCAGAGGCUGGAGGAUCAUUUCAGCCCAGGAGGUUGUGGAUACAGUGAGUUAUGACAUGCCCAUUCACUACAGCCUGGAUGACAAGCAAGACCCUCCCUCCAAAGAAAAUAAAGCUCAAAAUAAAAUAUGA